GGGCAAUGGUGGUGGUGGUUUUCUUUACUCACCUCUUGUCUGAGUCCUGGGGGUUGGAUAUGUCUGUUGCCUCUCUCCAGUCUGAAGUUGAAGCUCUAACUGAACAACUAAGUGAAGAGGAGGAGGAGGAAGAGGAGGAAGAAGAAGAAGAGGAAGAGGAGGAGGAAGAGGAAGAAGAAGAGGAAGAUGAGGAGUCAGGGAAUCAGUCAGAUAGGAGUGGUUCCAGUGGCCGGCGCAAGGCCAAGAAGAAAUGGCGAAAAGACAGCCCAUGGGUGAAGCCGUCUCGGAAACGGCGCAAGCGGGAGCCUCCGCGGGCCAAGGAGCCACGAGGAGUGAAUGGUGUGGGCUCCUCAGGCCCCAGUGAGUACAUGGAGGUCCCUCUGGGGUCCCUGGAGCUGCCCAGCGAGGGGACCCUCUCCCCCAACCACGCUGGGGUGUCCAAUGACACAUCUUCGCUGGAGACAGAGCGAGGGUUUGAGGAGUUGCCCCUGUGCAGCUGCCGCAUGGAGGCACCCAAGAUUGACCGCAUCAGCGAGAGGGCGGGGCACAAGUGCAUGGCCACUGAGAGUGUGGACGGAGAGCUGUCAGGCUGCAAUGCCGCCAUCCUCAAGCGGGAGACCAUGAGGCCAUCCAGCCGUGUGGCCCUGAUGGUGCUCUGUGAGACCCACCGCGCCCGCAUGGUCAAACACCACUGCUGCCCGGGCUGCGGCUACUUCUGCACGGCGGGCACCUUCCUGGAGUGCCACCCUGACUUCCGUGUGGCCCACCGCUUCCACAAGGCCUGUGUGUCUCAGCUGAAUGGGAUGGUCUUCUGUCCCCACUGUGGGGAGGAUGCUUCUGAAGCUCAAGAGGUGACCAUCCCCCGGGGUGACGGGGUGACCCCACCGGCCGGCACUGCAGCUCCUGCACCCCCACCCCUGUCCCAGGAUGUCCCCGGGAGAGCAGACACUUCUCAGCCCAGUGCCCGGAUGCGAGGGCAUGGGGAACCCCGGCGCCCGCCCUGCGAUCCCCUGGCUGACACCAUUGACAGCUCAGGGCCCUCCCUGACCCUGCCCAAUGGGGGCUGCCUUUCAGCCGUGGGGCUGCCACUGGGGCCAGGCCGGGAGGCCCUGGAAAAGGCCCUGGUCAUCCAGGAGUCAGAGAGGCGGAAGAAGCUCCGUUUCCACCCUCGGCAGUUGUACCUGUCCGUGAAGCAGGGCGAGCUGCAGAAGGUGAUCCUGAUGCUGUUGGACAACCUGGACCCCAACUUCCAGAGCGACCAGCAGAGCAAGCGCACGCCCCUGCAUGCAGCCGCCCAGAAGGGCUCCGUGGAGAUCUGCCAUGUGCUGCUGCAGGCUGGAGCCAACAUAAAUGCAGUGGACAAACAGCAGCGGACGCCACUGAUGGAGGCCGUGGUGAACAACCACCUGGAGGUAGCCCGUUACAUGGUGCAGCGUGGUGGCUGUGUCUAUAGCAAGGAGGAGGACGGUUCCACCUGCCUCCACCACGCAGCCAAAAUCGGGAACUUGGAGAUGGUCAGCCUGCUGCUGAGCACAGGACAGGUGGACGUCAACGCCCAGGACAGUGGGGGGUGGACGCCCAUCAUCUGGGCUGCAGAGCACAAGCACAUCGAGGUGAUCCGCAUGCUACUGACGCGGGGCGCCGACGUCACCCUCACUGACAACGUGAGUGAGCGUUUGGUUGAGGAGGAGAACAUCUGCCUGCACUGGGCCUCCUUCACGGGCAGCGCCGCCAUCGCCGAAGUCCUUCUGAAUGCGCGCUGUGACCUCCAUGCUGUCAACUACCAUGGGGACACCCCCCUGCACAUCGCAGCUCGGGAGAGCUACCAUGACUGCGUGCUGUUAUUCCUGUCACGUGGGGCCAACCCUGAGCUGCGGAACAAAGAGGGGGACACAGCAUGGGACCUGACUCCCGAGCGCUCCGACGUGUGGUUUGCGCUUCAACUCAACCGCAAGCUCCGACUUGGGGUGGGAAAUCGGGCCAUCCGCACAGAGAAGAUCAUCUGCCGGGACGUGGCUCGGGGCUAUGAGAACGUGCCCAUUCCCUGUGUCAACGGUGUGGAUGGGGAGCCCUGCCCUGAGGAUUACAAGUACAUCUCAGAGAACUGCGAGACGUCCACCAUGAACAUCGAUCGCAACAUCACCCACCUGCAGCACUGCACGUGUGUGGACGACUGCUCUAGCUCCAACUGCCUGUGCGGCCAGCUCAGCAUCCGGUGCUGGUAUGACAAGGAUGGGCGAUUGCUCCAGGAAUUUAACAAGAUUGAGCCUCCGCUGAUUUUCGAGUGUAACCAGGCGUGCUCAUGCUGGAGAAACUGCAAGAACCGGGUCGUACAGAGUGGCAUCAAGGUGCGGCUACAGCUCUACCGAACAGCCAAGAUGGGCUGGGGGGUCCGCGCCCUGCAGACCAUCCCACAGGGGACCUUCAUCUGCGAGUAUGUCGGGGAGCUGAUCUCUGAUGCUGAGGCUGAUGUGAGAGAGGAUGAUUCUUACCUCUUCGACUUAGACAACAAGGAUGGAGAGGUGUACUGCAUAGAUGCCCGUUACUAUGGCAACAUCAGCCGCUUCAUCAACCACCUGUGUGACCCCAACAUCAUUCCCGUCCGGGUCUUCAUGCUGCACCAAGACCUGCGAUUUCCACGCAUCGCCUUCUUCAGUUCCCGAGACAUCCGGACUGGGGAGGAGCUAGGGUUUGACUAUGGCGACCGCUUCUGGGACAUCAAAAGCAAAUAUUUCACCUGCCAAUGUGGCUCUGAGAAGUGCAAGCACUCAGCCGAAGCCAUUGCCCUGGAGCAGAGCCGUCUGGCCCGCCUGGACCCACACCCUGAGCUGCUGCCCGAGCUCGGCUCCCUGCCCCCUGUCAACACAUGAGAACGGACCACACCCUCUCUCCCCAGCAUGGAUGGCCACAGCUCAGCCGCCUCCUCUGCCACCAGCUGCUCGCAGCCCAUGCCUGGGGGUGCUGCCAUCUUCUCUCCCCACCACCCUUUCACACAUUCCUGACCAGAGAUCCCAGCCAGGCCCUGGAGGUCUGACAGCCCCUCCCUCCCAGAGCUGGUUCCUCCCUGGGAGGGCAACUUCAGGGCUGGCCACCCCCCGUGUUCCCCAUCCUCAGUUGAAGUUUGAUGAAUUGAAGUCGGGCCUCUAUGCCAACUGGUUCCUUUUGUUCUCAAUAAAUGUUGGGUUUGGUAAUAAA